AAACACAAGCACGCACACACCACUGGGAGAUCAGAUCUUCUAGCUGGCUCUCUGCUGCCACAGCUCCGCCGAAGGGAGGGGGUGGAAGAGGAGGACUAAACUCAGAGCUGAGAGGAGAGGCAGGUGUGUGCAGGUGCAUCACCUGGAUCAUGAGGUCACCCCUCUGCUGGCUCCUCCCACUUCUCAUCUUGGCCUCAGUGGCCCAAGGCCAGCCAACAAGACGACCAAGACCCGGGACUGGGCCCGGGCGCAGACCCAGGCCCAGGCCCAGGCCCACACCCAGCUUUCCUCAGCCUGAUGAACCAGCAGAGCCAACAGACCUGCCUCCUCCCCUCCCUCCAGGCCCUCCAUCUAUCUUCCCUGACUGUCCCCGCGAAUGCUACUGCCCCCCUGAUUUCCCAUCUGCCCUCUACUGUGAUAGCCGCAACCUGCGAAAGGUCCCUGUCAUCCCGCCCCGCAUCCAUUACCUCUAUCUCCAGAACAACUUCAUCACUGAGCUCCCGGUGGAGUCCUUCCAGAAUGCCACAGGCCUGCGAUGGAUUAACCUGGACAACAACCGAAUCCGCAAGAUAGACCAGAGGGUGCUGGAGAAACUGCCCGGCCUGGUGUUCCUCUACAUGGAGAAGAACCAGUUGGAAGAGGUCCCCUCGGCCCUGCCCCGGAACCUGGAGCAGCUGAGGCUGAGCCAGAACCACAUCUCCAGAAUCCCGCCUGGUGUCUUCAGCAAGCUGGAGAACCUGCUGCUCCUGGAUCUCCAGCACAACAGGCUGAGCGACGGCGUCUUCAAGCCCGACACCUUCCAUGGCCUCAAGAACCUCAUGCAGCUCAACCUGGCCCACAACAUCCUGAGAAAGAUGCCGCCCAGGGUCCCCACCGCCAUUCACCAGCUCUACCUGGACAGUAACAAGAUUGAGACCAUCCCUAACGGAUACUUCAAGAGCUUUCCCAAUCUUGCCUUCAUUCGGCUUAACUACAACAAGCUGACAGACAGGGGACUCCCCAAGAACUCCUUUAAUAUCUCCAACCUGCUUGUGCUCCACCUGUCCCACAACAGGAUCAGCAGUGUGCCCGCCAUCAACAACAGGCUGGAACACCUGUACCUCAACAACAAUAGCAUCGAGAAAAUCAACGGAACCCAGAUUUGCCCCAACGACCUAGUGGCGUUCCAUGACUUCUCCUCGGACCUGGAGAACGUGCCACACCUGCGCUACCUGCGGCUGGAUGGAAACUACUUGAAGCCGCCCAUCCCGCUGGACCUCAUGAUGUGCUUCCGCCUCCUGCAGUCCGUGGUCAUCUAGGCCCUACUCCGCCACCGGAUCUGCUCUGACCGCACUUGAAGGCUGGGGCCCAGGCACCUGUGCCGGCCAUUCGUUUUCUCUCUCUCCCUUUCUUUCUCCCAGCUUUGCCUCCCUUAUCCCACCCUCGAGGCAGGGAAAAGCCAUCUAUUCUUCUGCAGCCUCAGGAGCGAGACUUCAAGGACUCAGUUUGGUUCCACCCAGUUGAAAGACACCCAGUGCACACCCAAACUCCUGGCCUUCUGUGGUUUCCCUUUGCUCCAGAAACACAGAUGUGUCUAAAGACUUGGUGUCCCCUUCUCUCUCCUCCCCCACCCGCCACUCCUGGGUACAUCUGGGCCGUGGACUAUCUGAUCUUGGUCCUGGCCGAGCAAACAGCCCGGAGGUAAGGUUCAGAAAGUCCCCCUGGGGACUCCUCCAUCUUCGGCAGCUCUGGCUCAAAGAGGCCGAGAAACCCAGUUCUCCUGGGCCAAGGAUCCCUUCUGGCAAAGCUGCUGCUCCGCCGCUUGGUUCCCCGGCACCAGACAUCGCCCUGGCCCUGCUGGCCCGGGUAUCGGGAAGGAGGAGCGAGGGAAUGACGGAGGUAGGGUGCAGGGUCAGGGCUCCCGCAGGGGCCUGCAUCUGGCCAGCAGGACACAGGGAUGCGCAGGGCGCCCCCUUCUGUUCCAGGGUGAACAUAGCACACGCCCUCCUGGCUGGGCCUCAGGAGGAACAGCCAAGGAGAAGAAUGGCCCAAGGAACUAGGAAGCAGCCAUGGGAGAGGGGAAGGGUUCAAGCCCGGGAUGGGCCCGCGUGACGUCGAUGGGUCCUGCGGCCCCCUUGCCCAACCUCGGGUUUAGGGAGGAGGGUUCACAGUGUUUUUGUGGGGGCGGGGGAAGGAAGAGGCAGCCCCGCCCCCGCCAUCUGUUCUCCAUCAGUGUGCGCGGCCCAGCCAUUUCCACCCUCGGGAGGCGGCUCCUGAGAAACAGGGAGGAAGGGGCGGAGCACCUGGACGUCUCCCAGAAGCCCCUCCACGUUUGAAAAUGCGCCUCCUCCUCGGAGACAGACGCAUCGGUGCCACCUAGUGGCUGGUGGGAGUAACAGCUGGUCCCAGUCUUGCGCCUGGCCCUCUUCCUGGGGUGAUUUUCCUCGGUGGAGGAGGCCCGUGGGGUCCCAACACGGAAGAGCCAUGGGCCGUGUGCAUGGUGUCGCUCUCCUCUAGGGUCUAGCGGGCACAAACGUCCCCAGGCUGGGCUCAUUCCCAUCGUGAGUGAGCCCAGGUGAGGACAUAGUCGGCUCCCGUUUGUUGUAGGCCCUUCCCAGGUGCCUUCUCAGCUCCCUCAUCUGUAAACCGAGGAGGUGGAUAAGAUGCUCCCGGCCGGGCGCGGUGGCUCACGCCUGUAAUCCCAGCACUUUGGGAGGCCGAGGCGGGCAGAUUAUUGCCUGAGCUCAGGAGUUCGAAACCACCCUGGGCAACAUGGUGAAACCCCCGUCUCUACUAAAAUACAAAAAAAUUAGCCAGGCAUAGUGGCGCGCGCCUAUAAUCCCAGCUACUGGGAGGCUGAGGCGGGAGAAUCGCUUGAGCCGGGGAGGCGGAGGUUGCAGUGAGGCGAGAUUGUGCCACUGCACUCCAGCUUGGGCGACAGAGUGAGACUCCGUCUCAAAAAAGAAAAAAAAAAGAUGCUCCUCUGAGGUCCCUCCGGCGCUCAUGUUCCGAGUCUGCAGCUCCACACUUUAAAUCAUACUCGAAUGCAGGACAAGUCCUAAAUAUUUGCCCCUUCCCUUGCAGUAAUUUAUUUUCUGUAUGGACUGUCCCUCCCCCAGAGGCUUCCCCACCCUCCAUUGCCUGGCCCAGGUGAGCAGCUUGGCAGGUCUCCAAGUGGAACCCGGUCCAGACAGGGCUGCCUCGACUUCACCUUUCCCCCUAACUUCCUCCAAGGGAUGCUGCCCCUUCUCAGCCCCCUGCGUGUGUAUAUUGGUGGGAGGCAUAGAGGAUGGAUGUUCUAGAAAUGAGUAAGACACAGUGCCCACCCCCAAGUUAGGAUGAAAAAAGUUCCAGAGGUUUUUAAGAAAUUGGAUUAAGCUGGGUCCCUAACUUCAAGAAAUUCCCAUUAUGCUCCUUCUCACCUUUCUUUUUUGCUAAUUAUGGAAAAUAGGGCCCAUUUCAUCAUAGCCUCCUUCCCCCGUGCUCCACUACAAUCGCCGCAUUCUUUCUAGCUGCAGCUGGUUUCUUCAAGGCUCCUGCUUAAAGUCCACACGUUAUUAUGGCCGAAAGCAACCUGGUGCUUCGGCCUGGAUAAGAGCCCCUUCUGCAUCUUAUUCACAGCUUGCAGCCUCAGCCCCUUUGAUGAGGCCCUCAGGGGAGAGGUCAUUACCUUGAUCCUGCAAACCCAGACUCGUUGAGCAGCAACGCAAUCACCAUCAUCCCACUGCCCAAUCUAGAAUAUGUCUGCUCUCCUUUGCUCUCUGCAGCUGUAAGCCAGAGGGGAUUCAAGGUAAAUAGGCUUUACAGGCUCCCCUCCUCCAAACACACACAGAAUGGGCUGGUUUCUUUCAAGUUUAAAAAAAGCCCCCUUCUCCAUGCACAAGUUCAUUCCCUCCAUGCUGUCGUCAUCGACAUAUACAGGUGUGUACGUAGGUGUAUGUGUGUACUCUGCACGUAUAUCUCUUCUGUCUUGAAGACCCUGUUAACUUUGUGAAAUAACUUCCACAUUUCAACACACUUCACAGUACAGGAAAUAAAGUAAUAUGAAAAACACCCUGCGUGAACUCAACGGUGUGAACAGGUCAAGAAUAACACUUCAAAGUCAUCUUGCCAGCCAGGCGUGGUGGAUCACGCCUGUAAUCCCAGCACUCUGGGAGGCCAAAGCGGGCAGAUCACCUGAGGUCAGGAGUUCAAGACCAGCCUGGCCAACAUAGUGAAACCCCUUGUUUACUCAAAAUACAAAAAUUGGCUGGGUGCGGUGGUACAUGCCUGUAGUCCCAGCUACUUGGGAGGCUGAGGCAGGAGAAUUGCUUGAACCCUGGAGGCAGAAGUUGCAGUGAGCCGAGAUCGCACCACUGCACUCCAGCCUAGGAGACAAAACGAGACUUCAUUUAAAAAAAAUAAAAAUAAAAAUAAAAAUAAAGUCAUCUUGCCACCCACCCCCUACCAUUGAGCCACCAUGCCCAGCCCCAAAGCCUCUUAAUUGCUCUAACAAGAUGAGUGGGGAAAAGAUUAUACUCUUAAGAAAUUCCUACGAAAGCUAUCCAAAAGCCUUUUCUUUCCUCUUUUCUUAUUAUUUUUAAAUAGAGGCAGGGUCUCAUUAUGUUGCCCAGGCUGGUCUGGAACUCCUGGCCUCAAGUGAUCCUCCCACCUUGGCCUCCCCAGAGUGCUGGGAUUACACACGUGAGUCACCAUGCCCAGCCCCAAAGCCAUUUCUUGAAGAAUUUCUCGCAAACUCACAACCCUCAUGAAAAAUUAAUCCUCAGUUCCACGAGACUGCCCACCCACAGACAAAAAAAUAUAUAUAUUCCUAAAGUCGGACCAGAAAUCUGACAGCUGCCUUUGAAACCCAAAGCCUCGGGUUCUUUCAAGCUACAUGUACUAAAUUGUCGAAGGUCUCCCAGGAGCUCUGUACUGAGGCAGACACAGAAAGACACAAAACGGUCGUCUUUCCUGCCCAAGUAAAGCUUACAGACUAACUGGGGAGAUGUAGUGUGCAUACAAAACAGUAAAAGAGCCAUCUCAAGGACAGAGAGCAUAGACCAAGUCAUCUGGAAUGGUCUACAUGCCAUGCGGAAGUCCACCGAAGGGUUAGAACAGGGUGUCCCAGACUCUCUCUUCUGAGGGAAGGUUGGUUGCAAAAGUGGGAUUCAUGACCCUCCCAGGCUACACCAUCUUCUUUAGAAUGAGAACUGCCAGGUGACGCCCUCGCUGCUCCUACCUGGCUACUAAACAUCGACUUCGGUUCACUUCACGGAUGUUCAGUGGAUAUCGGUCACAUGCCAGGUCCCCAGCUACGCAUUCAAGGAUGGAUAAUAUACAUAGCAGCACAUCCUUGAGGAACUCAUACCUUGGUAAAGGGAAAGAAAUCCAUGAAUGGAUACCUCUGUGUCCUAAGUGUUUGUAAUAAUGCUGUGUGUCAGGCCUCUGAGCCCAAGCUAAGCCAUCAUAUCCCCUGUGACCUGCAUGUGCACAUCCAGACGGCUGGUUCCUACCUUAACUGAUGAUAUUCCACCACAAAAGAAGUGAAAAUGGCUGGUCCCUGCCUUAACUGAUGACAUUACCUUGUGAAAUUCCUUCUCCUGGCUCAUCCUGGCUCAAAAGCUCCCCCACUGAACACCUUGCAACCCCCACCCCUGGCCACCAGAGAACAACCCCCUUUGACUGUAAUUUUCCAUUACCUACCCACAUCUUAUAAAAUGGCCCCAUCCCUAUCUCCCUUCGCUGACUCUUUUCGGACUCAGCCCGCCUGCACCCAGGUGAAAUAAACAGCCUUGUUGCUCACACAAA